ACUUUCUCACAGUGUCUUUGGGCGUCUUCUUGACUGAAUCUGACUCCAUUGGAGGCUGUGGAGCAGGAAGCGCUGGACACAGUGACUUCACAUGUUUACACAAAAACCUGAAUAAGAUCCAUGGAACCCAGUGACAUGCCUGCUGGCUACCACUGCCCCUUAGACUCUGCCCCCUGGGAUGAGACCAGAGACCCCCAGAGCACAGAGCUGAUCCCCAGGAGAGCCAUCAGCCGCUCUCCAACCUGCGCCCGCUGCCGCAACCAUGGUGUCACCGCCCAUCUCAAGGGCCACAAGCGCCUCUGCCUCUUCCAGGCUUGCGAGUGUCACAAAUGUGUCCUCAUCCUGGAGCGCCGCAGGGUCAUGGCUGCCCAGGUGGCCUUGCGUAGGCAGCAGGAGGCGCAGCUAAAGAAGCACCUGAUGAGGAGAGGGGAAGCCUCUCCCAAAGCUCCCAACCACUUCAGAAAGGGAACCACUCAGCCACAGGUCCCCUCUGGAAAGGAGAACAUAGCACCCCAGCCUCAGACCCCCCAUGGGGCAGUCCUGCUGGCACCGACACCCCCCGGGAAGAACUCCUGUGGGCCUCUGCUGCUCAGCCAUCCCCCGGAAGCCUCGCCCUUGUCCUGGACUCCGGUGCCUCCUGGCCCUUGGGUCCCUGGACACUGGCUGCCUCCAGGCUUCUCCAUGCCACCACCAGUGGUGUGCCGCCUGCUGUACCAAGAACCUGCUGUCUCUCUGCCUCCCUUCCCUGGCUUUGACCCUGGCACCUCCCUCCAGCUGCCCACUCAUGGGCCCUUCACCACCUGCCCAGGAUCUCACCCAGUACUGACAGCUCCUCUUUCUGGAGAGCCCCAAGGGCCCCCUAGCCAGCCCCGCACACACUCAACUCUGAUACUCCAGCCCUGUGGCACCCCAGACCCUCUUCAGCUACAGCCACAGGUCCUGGGAAAGAAGUGGGAUCUAGGGCCCUGGGAGGAGGUUGAGCCUGGGGAAGGAAAAAGCAGGAAACUGAAGGAAGCAGGGGCUGAGGAACACUUAGAGGGUGGGCAGAAGCGGGGGUUCCCAGUCUGCUUGUCUCCCUUUCCCUUGCAGGCCUCUGGAGCCUCGUGCCUGGCCCGGACAUCUGGCCCCUCAGAGUGGCAGCUGCAGCAAGAGGCAGCUGAAGCCCUCGUGGGGCUGAAAGAUUCAUCCCAGGCUCCUCGUGUGACCCCUUCUGUGCCCCCCAACCCUGCCUGGAUCUCCCUGCUUCACCCCUGUGGCCCACCAGCUCCUGCUGGAGGAAGAGGAUUCCAGCCUGUUGGCCCCUGUCUUCGACCCAGCCCAGCCCCCUCUGUUGCUCUGCAUAUUGGCCGUCUGGGGUCCAUCUCCCUCCUGAGCUAGAAACCCAGAGAUGGAGGCUGUCUUGCUAUGGCAGGGAGGUGACAGCCUGCUGGCACUGUAUAUUUAGUGUCUUACUUAAGGAUUUAUGCAUGGAAUUUAAUGUAGUACAAGCUUCGGGCUUUUUUGUUUGUUUGUUUGUUUGUUUGUUUAAGCUUUCAGGUGCUUCAUUAGCUUUCAGUUCCUUUGGUAGUGUGGGCAUUUCCUUGGCUGACAGUGGAUAUUCUUGUACCCUUCUUGGGUCCUGGGAUCUCUUGAAAUCCCCAAUAAAGAGAGAGUUGUGCUAUUUAAGCUGACCAGUAUCUAUAAACGUGUUUGCAUGAGUUUACAUCCCAGGAUUCCAUGAUUCUGUAAAUGCCUAUGCAUUCAUGUCUGUCUCCAUGCAUGUGAAAACAGGAGAGUGUUUUCAUUUUGUGUCUAGGUUUGUGUGAGUAAGCAAGAAAUAAACCUUUGUUGUUGUAAGCCACUGAGAUUUGGAGAGUGUUACCACAGCCUAACCUAGUCUAUCCUGACUGACAGAAAGGACUUGUUCAUUUCGCUUCUCAAAGUGAAAAAUCUGUUAUCCAAUAGCUACCAUAGAUGAAAACAAACUUGGAUUUUUUUCUUUGUCCAAAUAAAAAAAAAUGAUGUAAAGAAAUAA